AGUCGGGCCGCACCCGCGUGAGGCGCCAGUAGCACGGCUCGUCGUGCUGCCACAGCCAGGACUUGCGCGUGACCAGGCGGCCCAGGCCGAAGAGCGGGAGGCGGCCGAGCAGCUGCAAGAGGCGGCUCUCGCGGCGCACGUCGGCCCAGGCCCGGACCGGCAGCCGGCGUCCAGAGAACGGCCGCGUCAAGGUCUCGUAGUCCACCGCGUAGAGCUGGGAGUCGCGCGGCCUGUUCAGUUGCUCCCGCAGGGCGCGCACGCGGCGGGCCAGCUCCGCGAUCAGCCGCGGACGCACCUUCUUCCGCGCCAUGGCGGGUCCGCGUCCUCAGCGGUCCGGCCGGAAGUCACCGGAAGAGGCCGGUGUCCCAGGCUAAAGUGUUCGGUCGCGGCCGGAAGCGAGGAAGAGGUCGGUCCGGCCAUGGCGCGGGUUGGACCCGGGAGGGCGGGGGUCUCUUGCCAGGGCCGGGGCCGGGGACGGGGCGGGAGCGGUCAGCGGCGACCUCCAACCUGGGAGAUCUCAGACUCCGACGCUGAGGACUCCGCCGGCUCGGAGGCCGCCGCGAGAGCCCGGGACCCAGCGGGUGAGCGCAGGGCGGCUGCCGAGGCGUUGCGGCUGCUGCGGCCGGAGCAGGUCCUGAAGCGCCUCGCGGUGUGCGUGGACACAGCCAUCCUGGAAGACGCCGGUGCCGACGUCCUGAUGGAGGCCCUGGAGGCCCUGGGCUGCGAGUGCCGCAUCGAGCCCCAGCGCCCGGCCCGCAGCCUGCGGUGGACCCGAGCGAGUCCCGACCCCUGCCCCCGCAGCCUGCCUCCUGAAGUGUGGGCUGCAGGUGAACAGGAAUUGCUGCUGCUGCUGGAGCCCGAGGAGUUUCUGCAGGGCGUCGCCACACUGACCCAGAUCUCUGGCCCAACCCACUGGGUGCCCUGGAUCUCCCCCGAGACCACCGCCCGGCCCCACCUGGCUGUCAUCGGGCUGGAUGCCUACCUGUGGUCUCGCCAGCACGUUUCCCGGGGGACACAGCAGCCAGAGAGCCCGAAGGUGGCCGGUGCCGAGGUGGCCGUCAGCUGGCCGGAGGUGGAAGAGGCCCUGGUACUCCUGCAGCUCUGGGCAAACCUGGACGUGCUACUGGUGGCCUCUUGGCAGGAGCUGAGUCGGCACGUGUGCGCCGUUACCAAGGCUCUCGCCCAGUAUCCCCUCAAGCAGUACCGGGAAUCCCAGGCCUUCUCCUUCUGCACAGCAGGGCGCUGGGCAGCCGGCGAGCCAGUGGCAAGAGACGGCGCAGGGCUGCAGGCGGCCUGGCGGAGGCAGAUCAGGCAGUUCAGUCGGGUCAGCCCAGCCGUGGCUGAUGCAGUUGUCACAGCCUUCCCCUCCCCCCGCCUUCUGCAGCAGGCGCUGGAGGCCUGCAGCACGGAGCGGGAGCGCAUGGGCCUCCUGGCCGACCUUCCUGUGCCGCCCAGUGAAGGCGGGCGUCCCCGCAGGGUGGGGCCUGACCUCUCCCGCCGCAUCUGCCUCUUCCUGACCACAGCCAACCCUGAUCUCCUGCUGGACCUGGGCUCCUGACCACACGUGGGACCACCAGGACAGCAUGCAGCCUUGGGGACAGACCAGACACCCUGGGCGGUGGGGGAGGACCCCCAGCCACAUGUGGACCCUCAGCCUGGGUGGGUUCUCUGGCUGAGCAGGUCUGACCUCAGGGGAAGGGUGGGUGGUUGCAGGGGAAGUUUUAGGUAGCUGGGAGAAGAGGGGCUUCUGGCUGGCAGAUGGCUGGCGGUUCCUGUGCUGAGUCCUGAACACGUAGGCCCCAGGGGAGGCCUCAGCAGCAGGGCUGUGCCCCCCCAACACACACACACACUCGGCAGGGACCAGAAGGCAGCUCCAGGGCCCCACUGCCACCUGGAGGCUUGGGGUGUGGCACCCUCAGCCAGAAGCAGUAGGGGACUCCCAAGGAUGUGGAGGGGCAGUGAGGCCUGGGAGAAGGCCCAGGCUGCUCGCAAGCCCGGCCUCUGCACGGAUACGUUUCAGCUCACGCCAUGUGGGUGUUAGACAUCAACUCUACAUUUAUUGCAGUCCUUUAAGUCUAUGACGGCGGGGCAGCCGCUGACAGCAUGCAGAGCAAGUUAGGAAAAACCGAGGCCCUGUGGGAACAGCAACGCGGGCUCCAGCCAGGCUCUCGUCCUCGCAGCCUCCCACAAGACCUGGGGCUCAGGGCAGCCGCUUCCCCACCCAGCACAGCAGCAGAGGGGCCCUAGAGCCCCCACAGAAAGGACUGUCCCAGCCUCGGGAGCAAGAGAUGGCUCCCUCCGGACGGGCCUCAUCCAACUCCGCCCUGGAGUGUGGCUGGAAGGAAGGGACAGAGAAAGAAGGGACAGAGGAAAGGGGCUGUCCCAGCCCAAGAAGGCAGUUCCACUGGGAAGUCAGUCAGGUCCGGCGGCAGCGCUUCCUCUGGCAGGGCCGAGGCUCGCGACUGCUGGGGUGGGCGGAGGUCGCUGCCUGGGGAUCGGACACUGGAGCCUUGCGGCGGCUGCAACUCAUGCUCAGGACCCAGCCCAGCUUGUUGUGUAGCACCUGCUUGAGGCCCGGCGGCAGCGGCAGACCCUCCAGCGUGUCUCCCGAGUCUGGCCGCAGCUGGCGCAGGCGGUGGCAGCACAGGUACUGGAGGGAAGUGGCGCUGGCACAGGAGCGGGUGACCUUCAUGCUGCUCCGGGCCGCCGUGGAGCACACCAUCGGGUAGAAUCUCUUGUUCUGCAGCUUGGUGGCUGCCACACCUGGAAGGGAGGGGCCCAGCCUGAACCCCAGGCAGGGAAGGGGCCAGCUACUGGGCGCAGCCCCUCAGACCUCACGCUACAGUCACCCGGGUGGGCAGCUGGCACAGCUGAGGCAAGGCAGGGUGCACGCGCUGGCCCUGCCACUCCAGCCUGGCCUCACUGUCCCACCCCCUGGGACCCUGGGGCCUCAGGCUUCUGGGAGGAACCCUUUCAGAAAACCUCAGUGUCCCCUGGGCUGGGGCGGGGUGGCUGCCUCCCUCGGGGUGACAGCUGAGAGGAGCUCAAGUCCUGUGACGGCCUCACCUAUACACUUCCUGUUCUUGAAAAAGGUGAGUGUGCCGUGCCAGGUGUCCAGGUGCACGCCAAUGAUGGAGCCCUGGCCGAACCGCGAUGAGAAGCUGGUCUUGUCGCCCUUGUGGUGGAGGAGGCCUGGGGGCAGCCAGGGUCGCAGUGAGCCCGGGAGCUCCAGGCUCGGCCCCGCCCCACCCUGGGCCUCACGCACCCGUGUAGGAGAGGCCCCAGCUGUCCUCAUCCCUGCCCAGCAGGCUGCAGAACGUGUGGCGGUAUUUGUCCAGGUCCACAUCCGACGUCCCGAUGCCCACCAUCUAGGAACAGGGGCCAGGCAGAGGGCGCGGGGCUGGGCUGCCGGAGCCAGGUUCCCCAGAAGCACCCUGGGCCGAAGCAACUUACCAUGUCGGUGCCGUAGACGGGAGAGGUCAUCUUGAUCUCCCAGAAGUGCUGGCCCUCCCCCAGCUCCUUGGUGCCCCGGAUGGCCGCUGUGCCGCAGCUGUACUCCAUGUGGAAGCUGACCUUACGGUUGUCACAGCUCAGCAGGGUGGCUGAUGACUUAUUUAAGUCAUCCCAGACCCAGUCGAAAUCUGCAAGAGAGGCCCAGGCUGGGGCAGCCCUGAGAGCUCCAUGGGGCUCUGCCCUGCCCACCCCCAGGCCCGCCCGCAGUGCAGUCCCAGCAGGGGCUGGGCCCCACGCUCACACUCGUCUUCCUCUCCGCAGCGGCAGUCCCUGCCCCGGUGGGCCGAGUGCAGGCUGCUACAGAAGGAGGCCUCGCUCUGCCCAGCACAGUCACAGAAGGACUCGCCGGUCACGGGCACCGCACUGGGGAUGGAUGGCGGCAGCGUGGAGUACUCGGGGUCGGAGUCCGAGUCGCUGUGCUGGGAGAGAAGGGCCGGCUGUUACUACCUGUUGCCCGCUCUCUACCCUCUCACCCUUGCCCUCUGUCCCUGUCCCACCCUGUCCCUGACCCACCCAGGAAAGGAUGGGGGUCCAGGCCUCCAGGGACUUCACAGUACCCCGAGCGCACAGCCCAGGCUCCCUCCCAACGGGCUCCGGCUCUGCCCCAUUCUGCAUGACCAGGAGGGCCCUGGAGGCCCAGCCACAGAGCAGUAGCCAAGGCUGCCUGGCCUCCAAGUGGUUUCUAGACGGUGGAUAAGCCCCAGGUCCACCCCACCUGCCCAGAGCUGAGAUGGUGUGGACACCUUCCCUGCUAGGCCAGCCCUGCAGGGGCCCCCAGGCAAGGCCACCACCCCCACACCAGGCCCAGCUGCAGCCACCCGGCCUCAGGGCAGUCCCCACCACACUGUGGCCCAACGACCUUCCUGUUACCUGAGCAGACCUGGCUCACCACAGGGUCCUACUGCCCAGUGCCCACUACAGGCCCCGCCCCUCCUGGUGCAGGUUUCAGCUGUCACCUCCCUGAGGCUUCUCCAGCCCCUUCACCCCUGUUCCAUUUUUCUUCUUUUGCUUCACUGAAGUUCUCCUUGGUCCUGAUUCUUGGCCUCCUCCCACCAGAACGUGAGCUCCUUGUGGGAGGCAGUGCCCCUCCCAGCCUCCUCCCUGUCACAGACUGUGUGGGGGCCACCCAGGGGCUGAAUGGACCAGGGGGUCAGCAGGGAGAGUGCUAAGUGGUGGCGGGGGGCCUGUGGCAGAGGCCUUGUGACAGUGAGGGUUGAGGGCUGGUCCAGAGAGAUGAUGUGAUCCCCAGGAGAAGCCACAGGGGACCAUGACAUGGGCGCCACCAGCUUCCAGGUGAACGUGGACCUAUCGAAAGCCAGCUUCAGGGCAGGACACUGUCCUUUCUGGAGGGGAUGGCCCCACCCCACAGACAAGGCAGGCCCAGACAACUCUACCCCACUGCCUAGAAGUGCGGGUCCCCAGAGCCAGGGUAGACCCCCUGAGUCAGGAGCCCGGGCACAGAACUGAGCACCUGCACUGCAGGCCCAGGGCCGGGUUCCCUGGAGAAGGAGAAAGACUGAAGCCACUGCCUACCUCCUGCCCACAACAGACUGCAGGCCCAUUUGGUGACACAGGACAAGCAGCACAUGUGUCGAACACUGCCGAGCCCGCAGGCACGCCUGCAUCCCACAGCCACGAGCCUGUGAGGCUCAGGCAUGUGACCUGCAGGAGCUGGAGGCGGGCGGGAAGGCAGGUGGGGGCCUCUCCCUGGCUGGAGCAGGGAGCUCCAGGAGACCUCAGGACGGCCCCCACCCGGUGGGUAAGGACCCUGUUUCCCAAUUUGCCCCCAAGGCCUAAUGGACCCACCGGGCUUAGGGAGUCCUCACUCAGAGGAGAGGAGCCCACCCCUCCCAGGACACCUGGCUGAGCCGGAACAGCAGCGCAGGGGAGCUGUGACAGCAGAGAGCAGCACCAGGUCACACAAGCAGCCGCCCCGGAAGGACACGGCCCAUGGUGACAGAGGACAAGCAGCAUGCGUGUGUCAGACACUGGCCUGGCCUGUGGACACGCCCGCGUCCCACAGCCAUGACCCUGCGAGGCCAGGAGAGACUGCUCCAGGGCACAUGACCUGUGGUAGCUGGAAGUGGGGCAGGGAGGCGCAGCCACACUCCUGCUCUGGUCCGAGGGAGAUCUCAGGAAACCGACUGGGAAAUCACCCCCCACAGGGACCCCCACCCCUCCCAGCCUCACUGCGCCCGUCAGGCCAGGCAGCUGCCCUCAGGGUCUGCCAAGGUGGGGGUCAGGGGCCAUGGGGGCAGGUAGCUCUGCCUGCAAAGCCCACAAGCAUGUCAGAUCACCUGGGCUGCAGACAGACAAACACCUGAGCUGUUCUGAAUACCUUCAGGUUCCUGGCCUCCCUGAGCAAGUGCAGAAAUUUUUACCUUCAAGGAUCAGGGUUUUUCUGUUUGUUUGUUUUUUAACACACAUAUAUGUGAACAAAGAGUAUGCGUUUGUACUGGCAGAAGAAGCGUCUGGUAAGACAACCAGCAAGUUAACAAUGGUCACCUCCAGAAAUGGGCUGGGUAAACCAAAGAAUUUUUUUGUUUUUGUUUUUUUUGAGUCAGGGUCUAGCUCUGUCACCCAGGCUGGAACGCACUGGUGUGAUCACGGCUCACUGCAGCCUUGACCUCCCUGGCUCAAGCAAUCCUCCCAGCUCAGCCUCCUGAGUCGUUGGGACUACAGGCACGUGCCACCACGCCUGACACAUUUUUUAAAUUUUUGUAGAGACAGUGUUUCACCAUGUUGCCCAGGCAGGUCUCAAACUCCUGGGCUCAAGUGGUCCUCCAGCUUCAGCCUCCCAAAGUGCUAGGAUUAUAGGUGUGAGCCACAGUGCCCAGCCCCGUAGUGGAGAAUUUCUGUUGAAUGAACCAAAAGCAACUGCCAACCUCUCCAUGCACCAUGUGUUUCAGAGGAGAAAGCACAGUGAAGAAUGCAGUGUGUUCUGAGGUCCUGUCACCCCUGAGGCUGUGUGUGUCCUUUGCCAAAUUAAAGAGUCUUACUGAAUGCGGUGCAUCCAGGAGACAGGCCCAGGUUUGGACUGGUCCUCUAGCCUCAGAAGCAUCUUUUUCUCCGACUGAUUCCGUGUUCAGGUAAUGUCUGCCUGCCUGCCUAGGGCAUCUCCACACCUUAGGCCAGCCACGUCCGCCUCGCCCGCUGGAACCUACCUGCCCAUCAGAGUCGUAGCCCCAGUUAGUGGAGCCUGCUAGAGCCACGGCCCGGGCAUCUGCGUCUCGGCGGGCUGCACUCAGGACGAAGUGCCAGGCCCUGCUGUUCCGGGGGCGUCUGGCCAUGGUGGAAAGAAUCUAGAAGAAAACACAGGCUCUGGGCAAAGGAAGACUCACAGCACUCCCAGCCCUGAGCUUCCAGGCUGGGCCACGGACCCACUCAAAGUGGGGACUGCAGGGGCCGCACCGGUGCCCAGCCAGGGCUCCAGAACGCUUCAGGAGCCCGUACCUCACUCCAGGAUCUGAGCAGCUCAAUAAAACCCAGGUAGAUCCUGUGAAACGCCA